AUGGGAGAGCCUCAGAACAUAGCCAGGAGGCUUCGGGAACUGCACAGCCCUGGCGACCCGGCCCUGUUCUCACUCUCGGUAAGGUCUAAUGAGGUCACAACCCAAGUGGAAAGACCCAGAGAUUCUGGAUUCUGGAUGUCAGAGGAGGGAGAGGAUCCCAUUUGUGUCUCUACACUACUUGUCUCCAGUGCCAUCUGGAGUUAUUCCAACCCUUACCCCCCUGAACAUUCUGUGCUAUCAGACAAUGAGUCGGUGUGUAACAAGCCCCUCACCCAAAUGGCCCCAGUCCACAAGCUUCAGGGAAAACAAGUAAAAACAGAAGAGAAAAUCAAAGGUGACUGGAUUCCUGCAAAAAAUGAAAGUGGCAGGCAUCUUUUCAUCAAAAGGGAAUUGGCUGGCACACUGAGAGUGCCUAUUUGUCAGACCCACGCAGGCGAUAAAGGAAAUGAAGGUGCGGAUCCCGGACCUUCUUCGCCGAGCCUGAACCGGCAGACCCCUCCCCAGGCCCCUGAAGACCCAGGAGUGAGCACCAAUGGGGGAAAGGCCGCGGAUCCCCUCAGGCUGCGGCGUGAUGGGCCGAGCUACGCCGGGGACCUCGGGGCUCGGAGAUUCGGUUCGACGGGUCCGGGGUGCGAUCCCCGCUCCGCGGAGCUCGCUCGGCCGUGGCUUUACCUGCGUGUGAUUGACUACAGGUGCUCAGCUCGCCCCCAGUCUGGUUCCUGCAGCUCCCCGGCUGCCAGCGGCGCUCAUGGAUAUACAGCCGGAACCCCUGGCCAGUGCAGCUCCCGCCGCUACCGGCCCCGCCCAAGUAACUGCCGCCACGCCCCUGACGACCGCUUCUGCCACGCCCCUAACCACGGAAACCGCUUGUUCAUUGGGCAGUUCAGCCGCUUCUCCACUUGCCCCGCGCGCUCAUUGCGUCUAGGAGGGGAUCCAUUGAUCAGCGAAGCUGUUCCUCAGAGUGGAGGCGGGAUUCUUAGGGGAGAGCUCCUCAGCAAUUGGUUACAUUUGACGGCUUUAGUCCAGGGACCCAGACGCUACUGGAUAAGGCCAGCCCGGAGUGGGCGGGGAAAGGGGAGGAGGGCUAGAAGGUGGGUCGUGUUUGAUGUCGAUGGGGGCGGGGUGAAGAGACGGGUAAUUGUGACCGCAAACUGCUUUAGAGGGCUGGGGGUGAAAUUUGAGGUCAUAUCCCGGGAGAGAGGAAGAAGGGUCGUGAGUCACCGAACCCGAAGGAGAGGAAAAGAUGUGGAGGCAGCGGUCUAUGGCCUCUUCCAGCUCCGGACGGGGGAUGGGGACGCUCUGGGCAAUACGGGCCUCAGUUAUUGUCCCACUGUCCUUUCAACCCUUAACCAACCCAGUUGGAGGCCGCCUGGAAGAAUGUAGCCUUGGAACUAGGGCCUGGAAUUGGGGCUCCUACCGGUUGUGUGGGCUUGGGCAAGUCACUUAACCUUCCCGCAUGCUCCCUUCACUUGGCAACUGAGGGUAACAAUAGUAGUUGAUGAGAAGAUUAAAUAAACUCUGAUAAAUGCCAACAGUGGCUGGCACUCAA